GAUGCAGUGAGCUAAGAUCACACCACUGCACUCCAGCUUGGGUGACAGAGCAAGACCUUGUCUCAAACAACAAAACCCAGAAGUCUGAAAAGUUACAACGUGAAAGAGGACAUCAAGUGAAGGGAAAAAUCAUGGUAGGAAAGAAAGAUGAAGCCAGCAGUCCCCACUCACUGAGCUAGAAGACCUGGAACACUAGACAGAGGUGGUUCUGAGCUUCCUAGUGGCUGAGGAGAGGAGUGAAAGCGGACCCCAGCCCCCGAUCUAGCAUGGGAGGAUGAAAGCACAGCCAUUGUUCUGGAGACACUUUCUGGUUGUCAUUAUACAGGCUCCCUGGAGGAUGUGCCUCCUCCCCCUUCAGGAUUUAGCUCCUCUACUUCCCCUGGGCUGGUGUGGGCACAUUGUCUGUGCUUUGACAGUCCCUAGAUCCCAUGUGUUCUAGAACCUUCUCUCCCAAAGCAGAACUUUUUUUUUUUUUCCUGUUUUCUGUUUUUUAAAUCUAUCUCAGCCUCCUGACAAGCAAUAAGAUUUGGAAUAUUUGUUGAGGGGAUAAAUAAAUGAACUCCUUAGUCAGUGCAGAGAUCUGUGCAUUGCGGCCAUUUCUUGAGCAUUGCCGCCAUUUCUUGAGCAUUGCCAUGUGCAGGUCAGAGACGUGGGAGCCCCCACACAGCGGGGAGGAGAGCAGAGGCGGAGGAUGGGGGGGCUGGGCUAACCCAGGCUUUCCAAGCUGUGAUGGGGCAGGAGCUUCUCCACUAGCUCGAGGGAGGGGGAACUUGGGCUCUGGGCGCCUGUUUUGGAGGUUGCAUCCCUUUGAGGGGCGCUACGGGUUGCAACUCACGCAGGAAAGAUUCCCCUCUCGGGCCUGUUUCCUCUUCUCUCAACCAGCGAUGCCAGGCUGAGGCUGUAGGUUCGAGAAUCACGUAGGUAAUGGGCCUGGCACAUAGUAGGCUCUCAAGAAAAGGUUGGAGCCUCUUGAGGAGUCUGCCUGUGAUGGAUGCGGAGCGCAGACCCAGCGCAGUGCGGCGAUUCGCCCAAGGUCACACAGCCGCCCCCCCCAAUUCGGACCCCGGGCGGCCUGACUCCGGGGGCCGGGGCUUGUCGGGAGCCAGCGUGGGGGCGAGCAGUGUUUGGAAGAGCGGCCGCGGCAGUGGGUGGGAAGGGGCUUCUAUUUUGGAGCGGGUGAGAGGAGCGGGACACGCGGAGGAGGAGUGGCCAGACGCUAAGGACUGGAGCUUGCAGGACACGGACGCCUUCGUGCUCGUCUACGACAUCUGCAGCCCGGACAGUUUCGACUACGUGAAGGCCCUGCGGCAGCGCAUCGCGGAGACCAGGCCGGCGGGCGCGCCCGAAGCGCCCAUCCUCGUGGUAGGCAACAAGCGGGACAGGCAGCGGCUGCGCUUCGGACCGCGGCGCGCGCUGGCCGCCCUAGUGCGCAGGGGCUGGCGCUGCGGCUACCUCGAGUGCUCCGCCAAGUACAACUGGCACGUGCUGCGUCUCUUCCGCGAGCUGCUGCGCUGCGCUCUGGUGCGCGCGCGCCCUGCACACCCGGCCCUGCGCCUGCAGGGGGCGCUGCAUCCCGCGCGCUGCAGCCUCAUGUGACCCGAUCGGACAGUGCCAUCCAUGGGCCCCACCUUGUGACUGGGACAAUCAGGGACCUGGAUUGGACGGGAUCGCCCAACUUCACUGGGACUGGACAGGGAAGUCUCCGCCCUGAUUGGAUGAGGAAAGCUCCAACCCAGUCUCCUAAGCGACUGGCCCCCUUUUGAACCUCAUUGGACCCAACCAGGUCCCAAGCUCCAUUGGAGAUGACCAGUCCUUUCUGGGACCUCAAUGGGUCACAAUCCCAUUGGAUGGAAAGGACUUGGCUAUGAACUUGACUGGAAACACGCAGCCUGCUCCUGGAGCUUCACUGGACAUAUUCUUUAUGCCACACCUACCACGGGAUAAUAAAAGGGAAAAUAAUUUGA